GGAAGCCGGGGAUCCGCGGCCAUGACGGUGCCGGUCCGCGGCUUCUCGCUGCUCCGCGGCCGCCUUGGCCGAGCGCCGGCGUUGGGCAGAAGCACAGCACCCUCCGUAAGGGCACCGGGAGAGCCCGGGAGUGCGUUCCGGGGCUUUCGGAGCAGCGGUGUGAGACAUGAAGCCAUUAUUAUAUCAGGAACCGAAAUGGCCAAGCAUAUCCAGAAAGAAAUACAGCGAGGUGUGGAAUCAUGGGUUUCCCUUGGAAACAGAAGACCUCACCUCAGUAUAAUUUUAGUGGGAGAUAACCCAGCAAGCCAUACAUAUGUCAGGAAUAAGAUAAGAGCUGCCUCUGCUGUAGGUAUUUGUAGUGAGCUCAUUCUAAAACCUAAGGAUGUUUCUCAGGAAGAACUUUUGGACGUAACUGAUCAAUUGAAUAUGGACCCAAGAGUCAGCGGUAUAUUAGUUCAGUUACCACUACCAGACCACGUUGAUGAGCGAACAAUAUGCAAUGGAAUUGCCCCAGAAAAAGAUGUAGAUGGAUUUCAUAUUAUCAAUAUUGGAAGAUUGUGCCUUGAUCAGCAUUCUCUCAUACCUGCCACUGCCAGUGCUGUUUGGGAAAUAAUAAAAAGAACAGGAAUUCAAACAUUUGGAAAAAAUGUGGUUGUGGCUGGAAGAUCCAAGAACGUAGGGAUGCCUAUUGCCAUGCUUUUACACACUGAUGGAGAGCAUGAACGGCCAGGAGGUGAUGCAACUGUGACAAUAGCUCACAGAUACACCCCCAAAGAGCAACUGAAGAUUCAUACGCAGCUGGCAGAUAUUAUCAUAGUUGCUGCAGCCCCAGUGUCUGCCCUUCCCUGCCCUGGUCUGGCCCUGAGAGGCUGACUAAUGAAGAUGGCCUCACCUGUGUUCCUCUGACACUGGCUCCCAGCAAGGUUUGGCACUAGUAGGAUAUCUGAAGGAGAAGAAGAGAAAUGUCAAGUCAUGGUGUUUCUUCUCUACUCUUUUCCACUUCUACUGUCUUUCUCUUCCUCCUGCAUCGAUAGCUUUUGCUCAGCAUCCUUUCCCCGACAGCUAAGGCUCUCACUGGGCUGCAGUAACACCAUUUCCUCACCCCUACAGACCUAGGAAUGGUACAAGCUUCCUCCAGUUUCUAAUCUCUAAGAGCUGCAACAGCUUUUGUUUUUAUCUUAGCCUGAAUAUAUCGCUGUAAAAAUUAUUUCAUUACUAUAUGGGGUGGAUUCUGUUUCCCAUGGAGAUACCGACAGAAGCAGAUCUGUAUGAAGUAAAGGCACAAAUCAAGAACCAUUCCUGGGGGAAGAGCAUCCCGAGCAGAGGAAACAGCAGAUACCAAAGUCCUUAGGCAGGAGCAUGCUUGAUGUAUUCCAGAACACAGGUCUUUGACGGCUUAUUAUAUUACUCUGAUUUUAAUAAAAUAUUAAUAAAUUAUGAGGAUACUAGUAAGAAAUGUUGUUGGGAAGGUAGCCAGGGUUAACUCAUGAAGGACGUUGUCGGCCAUGGUUAGGAUUUUGAUAUAAGCCAAGAAUGGCUGACAGCAGAUCAACAUGGUCUGACUUAGGUUUUAAAGGACUGAUCACACCUUUAAAAACAUAUCAGACCUCAUGUCUGCAGUUGUGUCAAAAACUGACUUUAGAGGUGUAAAAGUAGAAACAGAGAGGAGAGGUAUUGCAAUUUCAUUUAAUGGGUCUAGAUUUUGCUCUAAUUUGUUUUGUAUUUGAACACAUAGUUUCAAUCAAAUUUAAUAAAAUAUCUGAUUCUUCUAUAGGCCCUUUUCUGGAACCUAGAACAUAUACAUGACUGCAGGAACAGUAGUUGGCUCCUCAUAGAGUAAAAAUAGAAAUGUUCUUUUUCCCAGAAAAAAAAUCAGUAAGCUGGUACAGAUAACCAUACCACAUUGCCUGUUUUUCCAAAAAAUUACAUUUGGGUGAUAUCAAAUGCAAAUUUUUGAACUGCAUUGACAGAAGUCAGGCAUGUUUAGAGAGUUAGUAAACUUUUUCAGACCACAGAUCAGCAUUAAGUGAAAUACUGCUUCAGCCACUGAUACCUUCAUGGCAGAUAAGUAUUAUACUGACUUCUUUUUAGAGACACUUCUGUUCACACACAAGACACAGAAUUUGUUGAAUAAAGAGGAAUUUGAAUGCUCAUCUUUGUCCGUUUCUAACCUUAGGAAGAAUGAAGUUUACAUUAUCCUUAAAAGGUAUUAUUUGACUAAUGUUAACAGCUUGUACAGAAUAUUUGACUAUUGUCCUUAGAUAACAUUUAUCAAAUAUUAUAUUGAAUGAGUAUUUUAUUCUAGUGGAGGAAAAUCUCUCAUCAUGCCUUCCUACUCGUGGUUUGUUUUAUUAUUAUGACAAAUGGCACAUGGGUGAUCACAAUCCACUUGCAAGAAACACUGAUAUUCUCUUGUAACUAAGUCAAAGCUUAUGCCAUAAUGCCAACACUGUUGUCCUCCUUGAGUUUAUCCUCUCUAGCUUUCUUUGUAAAGGCCUAAAUCAGCCUUGAGUACAGAUAUUUAAAAAGAAGACAGGAAAAGAAAAAGAAAAGGAAAAUAAAGGAACAGAAGGACAAGGAAGACUCAAGCCUAUAUAAAAUAAACAAGACAGGAGCCAGGAGGUACUCAAGCUUUAGGUGUGGUGGGUGUUGAGGCUGUCCCACAAGCAUCCCGCUGAGGGUAUUUUCUUACCACCAGAGGGCGCCAGUCAGGUGAGCAGCUACUUCAGAUGUAGCCAAGUUGGCCAUACACCAUGCUAAUACUAGUUAGAAGACAUUUUAAACAAAGACAGUGGGAAGAAGUCCUGUUCCUUGCUUUUUUAUUUCACCUUUAAUGCCUCUUACUAAAUACAAAAGUAUGUUGAAUGUAGAAGACAGAUUUGUAUGUAGUUCUGCAGUCUUCUUGAAGAAAUAAAUAUUUAGCCAAUGGGAAAUUUAGGGGAAGAAAAUUGAGAAUUUAUAAGAAACAACUAAAGAUUGCUACAUUUCCAGUUAAUUAAUAAUCACCUGGAGAAGUUAGGGAUAAAACAUGUAGGCAUUUAUAAAUUAUAGAAAGAAUGUGAGUGAAUAUAAAAAAUAAAUCCCAUAUAACCAGACAAUAGGAAUAAAGUAUUGCCAGAAUGACCAUAUCAUGCAUUGUGUGUGGGAACUAAACAAAUACAAAUAGCAGUGGGUAUUUAAAGGAAAUAGUGAUCUAAUGGCAGAGGUAGCCAGAACGGGGAGGGCUAGAUCACUGUCAUAAUGAGAAUGUCAGCAUAUAUGGAAACAACCUCAUCUAGGAGAACUCAGGGUAGAAGGAGGAGGAUUGCGUGAUAUAUAUCAGAAAGAAUGAUAAUGUCUGAGAGAUGAGAGUGAAGAAUGUGGUAAUGAAAUCUUGACACAAGCUUGAAGAAAGUAAAAGAGGAAAUCCUGUGUGAAGAUCCUGAGACAUGAAUAUUAGCUUAUUUAAUAUUAAUGUCAUCCCUCCAGUUUCUCAUAGUACUACUCCUACUGGCUUAUAUAUCACUCACCUUUUUAAAAUUGCCCCCAAAAUUGAGAUUUAGACUCAGUUAGAAGCUUAGAUCUGCAGAAUCAGACCCUGUCACACUAUGCAAUUAGAAGUAAGUAGCUUCAAGUCCCUACUCAAAGCCAAAUCUCUGAGUUCACAGAGAGAGUUAACAAGUUUCUAGAGUACUUUAAUGUACCAUGGUUAUAGCACAUAGUACCUGUUUAUAGUUGUUAUCUUCAUUAGACUACAGCAGGUAAAGGCGUGGUAUUUUUUUUUAAGCUUGCUAGGUAAGUGCUUAGAACAAUAUCUAACACAUAGUGGUUGCCCAGUAAAUGUGAGCUGUGUUGAUUUUGAGAUUAUAACUACAAUAAGAACUUUUUCAAAUUGAUACAUAUUUAGCCGAUAUAAUCUAAUUUUUUAAGAUGGAAUUAUUCUAGUUGUUGGAUUUACACACUGUAGCAUUAUUUUUGGGAACUACCAAAUUAUUCCAGUUUGUCAUCAUAAAGUAGUUGCUAAAGCAAUAAAAAGUGAAAUAUUUAUUCAUGAAAGAGUAGUUCAUGUCAUUAAGUGUAUGAAUGGAGUGAUUUAGGUGUAAAUGUUAAGAUUAAGAAAUGAUGGGAAAGGUGGCCGGGUGCAGUGGCUUACAUCUGUAAUCCUAGCACUUUGGGAGGCUCAGGUGGGUGGAUCACCUGUGGUCAGGAGUUUGAGACCAGCCUGUCCAACAUGGUGAAACCCUGUCUCUACUAAAAAUACAAAAAUUAGCCAGGUGUGGUGGUGGGUGCCUGUAAUCCCAGCUACUCAAGAGGCUGAGGCAGGAGAAUCACUUGAACCCGGGAGGCGGAGGUUGCAGUGAGCCGAGAUCACACCACUGCACUCCAGCCUGGGCAACAGAGCAAGACUCUGUCUCAGAAAAAAAAAAAAAAGAAAAAAGAAAAAAAGAAAUUAUGGGAAAGGUGAAGAAAGAGUAAGGAGACUAUUACAUCUAAAGAACAGUAAGAGUACUGGAUGGUUGAAAGGGGAGGAGCAGUUUAGGGAAAGGCUAAAUCAGCUUUGCACAAGCUACUGAUAAAGAAGGGAAAGCUAGCCAGUAUCAAUUCUAAGAUCAUGUUGGAGAUCAUUGGGCUUUCUCGUAUCUGCUUUAAGGAAACUGUAGGCUAUCCUAAGUCUGUAAAAUUCUAGGAAUCUUCAUUAUUCAGCAGGAUAGGCAAGUUUUUUUAGACAUUGUCCACAUUACCCUCCACCCAUCUGAGUAAACUCUGAAACUAUAUUCAGGAAAUGAGCUGCUGAGUCAAUGCCACUUGCAUGUCAAGCUCUGGAUGCAGUGUCACGGUGGUGAAAGCUGGCAUUUUUGGCCACUAAGCCAUCCCUUCCAGCAUGACGAAUGAACCUUCACAGUUGUAACUUUAGAGUGUCUAUUGCAACACUUUUAAUGACAGAUACCAUGAUAUAAAACAGGAUAAAUGGGCAAUUUAGUAACUCAGAAUAUUCAUACUUACUUGUCAUAAAGUACAAAGUGACCAACGAAUUUCCUUUCACCACUUCUCCAAUCAUAUUAUCAAGUCUUAGAAACACUCCCAUCAAACAUUAUCCUAGGGCUCAAUAGGGUUUUCCCCCGGGUGUAUUUCCUCCUCCUUGAAACAGGGUUCGUAAUUUUCAGGAAACCAGGACAUGGAGAAGUUCCAAGGGGUGGGGCAAGGAAAUAGCUCCACCAUCCCCACAGCUCAUGCAACCCGGGAGUACAACUUGCUCACUUACGGCCCUGAGUGCUUCCUGAGUGAUGCCAGCACAUUUCAUGGCUUCACUCAUACUAUAGUCCUUUCCAUAUCUCAUUUCUUAUUUGUUAUUGUCCAGCUUGUCCUCUUUUGCUAGCCUCUGCUACUCCACUUAAGGGUUCCUUCCCUCCUUCCUAAAAGUUGUCAUUAUUUUCAUGGUACAGAGUAGUGAAAAUGCACAGGCCUUUCUAAAGUAAGAAUUCCAGGAUUUAAAUUCCAGCUCUGAGACUUGCUGAUUGUGAGCUUGGUCUCAUUUCUGAAUCUCAAUCUGUUCAUUGAUGUGAUUUAAAUGAUAAUAAUAAAAGUAACCUUUCAUAGCGAUGUCUACUUUAUAUUUUUGAUCUUAACUAUGCUGAUCUAAGUAGAAUUUCCCAUAUCUAAAAUGAUGCCUUUUACUUAUUGAAAGGCAUUUUAGUGUGGUUUAUGUGUAAUACCAAAUAAAGAAUAUUUAACACUUCUCAAAAAAAAACCUUUUGCAUAGUGUAAUCAAGCUAGCCAAUCCAUGUAAAGAGCAUAGCACAGUGCCCAGUAUAUUGCAAAUAUUCAAUAAGUGUUAUGUGUUAAUGUAUUCUAUGUUAGGCAUUGCAUGUGAAUAUUUAAACAAUUUAGAAAUGAUAAAUCAGUUGAUUAUUAAGCUACAACUUAGCAUAACUAAAAGAAUAUACUUCUUGGUUGCUUUUGAUACUAAUACAGUAUCAGAGUAGAGUAGUUCUUAUAAGCAUAAAUAAAUUAAGAAGUGACUUACACAUGAGGGACCAACUUUAUGGAAACUUUAUUUUUAUACUUAAGAUGUAUGCCUUCUCAGGAUGACAUCAGCACUUGUUCAUAGAUGUGUAUUAUGUUGUUCCCUGGAUGAAUUCCUUAUUGCCUCUCCCUCCUUUGGAACAACCUGACUUUGAGAGGGGAGAUAGGGAAGGCCGAGGCACUUAGAUGAAAGGGAUUUUUUUCUCUCAGGCCUUUAUCCACCGUCCCAGUCUCCCUCUCUCUCUGUUUCUACCUCAUCUUCCCACCUCAGGCUAUUCUGGCCCUCACAACCCAUGCCCAAAGCCUAAGUUACUAAGUAAGCAAAGCUUCCCUGGCCUGCAGUGAGCUUUGUCAAUACCUGAGAGGGCAGCCUGACUACUGAUAUUUUUCUUGGUGUCAGUAAUACAUCCUUACUGCAAAAACUUAGAAAACUUGGACAAUAGAGAGGGAGGGAAAGAACCUUAAUCCCAACCAAAGUGAAAUAAGGUAAACAAUUUGAUGUUUGACCUUGUACUGUUUUAUAUUUAUACAUAGAUCUAAAUAUUUAAACAAUUCUUUUGCCUUGUAUAUACUAUUUGUAUUUAGCAGCUCUACACCAUGUACGUGCUUCUUCAUAAAAUGCUUUCUUCCAAAACAGACUUCUAAUGACUCUAUAGUAUUGAGUGCUAUGGAUAUACUAAAUUUUAUUUAUUCAGUUCUUGACUAUUGGACAUUUAGAUAGUUCCCUGAGUUUUACUGUUAUGAAUAAUGCAGCAAACAGCUGUAAACAUCUUAGAUUAUUUGCAUCGUAACCCAUAAUAUUUAUCGUAUUGGUCUUAAGUUUAUUUUCUUAGUAAUUAUUACUUAUAUUCUAAAAACAAAUGAACAUUUAAGCUUGGUGUAUAAUAAAGGCUUACACGUGUGUUUAAUAUUAAAGCAUAUUUCAUACCUUACCUGUGCAUUUAUGUAAAGUUUUAACAGAGAGAGGAGAUAGCUGUGUCUCGUUUGUAACCCAUUCUCCAGGCCUGUUACCAUUACCAAUCAGUAUACUAUGAAGCUUUAGAUCCUUAUCUUUCCACAAGAGAAGAUAGAAGCCUAGUGUGUGGGGAAGGGGACUCAAAUAUGAAGUGGGGUGUAGUAUCAAAAGAAACGUGGUCUUUAAAGUAAAGAGGGUUUGGUUUUAAAUUCAAUUUUAACUUUAAAAAUCACAUCUAACUCUCUGGGCUUUAUUUUCAGCUAUCGCAAAAUGGAGGUAGUAAUACUAGUGUUUAUAAACUGUCAUGAGAAUUACAUCCUUAGCACAUAAUGGCUACUAAGUGAAGGUAGUUUCCCUUCCCUUCAUUCUCCUAUUGUGUGGUGAGCUCCUAUUGUGUGGUGAGCCAAUCACUAAAAUUACAACAUGUUUUAAAUGAAAAUAUAUGAAAAUUUAUUAUCUAUUAUGAAAAGACUUUAACUUUCUAAUACUUUGGUAAUAUAGACUGUACAAAAACAUGUACAAACUUUUAUAUGUUUCCUUGCUCGUUAGCCUCAAAUAAGCAAAAACAUUUUUCCAAGAUCGAUCACCUCAGAACCAUCACAAAGUUUUAUUUUUUUUUCUUCAUUUGACUGAGACCCUUGUGUUUUUCUCCUCAACUUGUUCUAAUUACAGGGACUUUUGAAAAGGGGGAAUCUUUUCAUCUCUAGGUUUUUUCAAUCUAUGGUAUUAGUACAUGGUUAGCUGAGGUUGAUUUUUUUUCUUUUGAGGCUCUUCUCUCAACACAUAUAUAUGUACUAUUUCUGAUUUUUCAUGAGUAAAACAAGCAUUGAUAGCAAUAUCCAAAAAAGCUUCAGUAAAGAACAAUUUAUAUCAAAGAUCUUUCUUCACUGUGGAGAAUCACAGACUUCCUUGGAAAUAUACUUUAGAUGGUCAAAUGAUACAUCAUUUAAACUUAAUUCUAUUUGGGUCCAUGCAUGUAUAUCAUGGGCUUGGGAAGAAGUGAGGUUCUUCCUUUCAAGUUAUGUCUGUAGCCUUUGAUAUUAUCACUUUGUUAUAUUUUUAUGUCCAGGUCUUUAAAAGGUUUAUGUUAGGAAAUACUUAAAUAUACCCAAAAGUGUAUAAGAAUAAUGUUAAUUAAAACGUUAACACUUAUGUUAUCAAUACCUAAAUUUGACAGAUGUGAAUAUUAUGUAUAUUUUCAAUCUACCUGUUUUAUAUUUCUAUAACUUGCUUUGUUUUGACUAAUGCUAUGACUUUCAAGUUUGCCCAUGCUAAUAGAUGUAGCACUAUUUCUAUAAUACUCAAUUGCUGAGUAUCCAUUUUCUGUUGAUGAAUAUGUAUGCUAUUUCCAAUAUAUUGCUAUUAUGAACAGUUCUGUAAUGUUUAAGUUUAUACAUAUUUUCUUGGAGACUCAUUCAUUCAUCCAUCCAGCAAACACUAAUUUUGCCACUGGUACAUAUUAAGCCAUAUAGCAGGCAUUAGAAAAAUAUAUAUAUAUAAACUUGGUUCAGCUCUUGAGAAGUCCAGACACUAGUGGAGGAGAAAGAUGUGCAAACAAAUUAGUGUAAUACAGCUUGCUAGUGCAAUAUUAGAUACAUGUAUGUAUGUAUAUGUACAUGUCUAUCUGUUUAGAAAAGGAGACAGUGUGUGUGUGUGUGUGUGUGUGUUUACGUGUGUAAGAGACACAGAUAGAUUGAAAAAUAAAAACAGAGAGAGAGAGCAUCAUUGGAGAGGAAGUAAUAGCUCUUUUCCUCUGACUCUGAAAAGUACAUGAAUGAGUCGGGUUUCAUCCCACAGAAUGAACAGAAAUUCACUAGGCAGAAUAAAAGGCAAUGAGACUUCUGGCAGCUUAGAGCUAUAAAAUGCUAUGCAUAUAGCAAAGAAAAUAUUUACUCUUUCAAAAUGACAGGUGCCUGUCUGUGAGUUGUGAAAGAUGAAGCAUAACAUUUAGGAAAAACCAGAUAUCAUAAUAAAUUAAGAAAUUUUAAUUUUAUCCUGUAGGUCAUAGGCAACCUUUAAAUAAUUAGAAGCACUGAAAUAACAUCAUAUUUGAAUUUUAGAAAGAUCACUUGGAUAGCCCCUGUGCAGGGAUAAAACUGGAAGUAGCAUUGAUGUAGUUCUACACUAAUACAGGAGUAGAUGAAAGUGAGAAGGAAAAACAGGAAGUAGACUAGAAAGGCUUACUGGCUUUAGAGACUAAGUAUAUGGUGUUGCCAUUAACAAGGAAGGUAUAUAGAAAGGAAGCAAAGUUUGAGAGAAGUAAAGAUGAGUGAGUGGGAGGAGAUAAUUAAUUCAAUGUGAAUGUGUUGAGUUGAUGACACUAGGUGUUAUAUUCAGGUGGAAAAGUCCAGGAGAGGGUUGAGAUAUGUGGGUGUGGGGUUUGGGAGAGAGCUCUGUUCUGGAGUGAUAAUUUUGGAAGUCAUUAAUAUCAGGGAUAUUGGACACGAAUUCAUGGAUAAAACCAUCUAGAAUAAGUCUGUUUAUAGUGCAUGGACUGAAUUUCUAUUUCAGACAUCUUUGAAGUGUGUUGGUUGAUAUGGUUACUUCUAUAACAUUGCCUUCUUGCUUCUGUAUACCUAGUGCCAAUGAAAGAUAGCCUAUUCUUAUUCCAGCAUCUACUUCAAUUGAUCGUAUAAGAAAAAAACUGGUAUUUUUAUGAAGCUUUGUUGUUUCAUACCUGUUGUUCUUUUGUUACCCCGACCUUUAUCGGCUUGAAAGCAUUGUUUGAGUAACAUGAGAGAAUGUAUUUGAUAAACCAAAAUGUGCCAUAUAGUGGAGACAAAAUUGUGUCCUAAAAAUAAAAUGAUGGACUUUACUUCAUAAAUGUUUAAUUUUUUACAUGUAAAAGAUUAAAUUUAAACUUCUUUAAUGUAAUGUAAACUUCUUUAAUAAAUGUUCCCAGCAGGCAGAAUUUUUUGUUUUUGCUUGCAUUUGUAGUCUUUGCAUACUGGAUUUAUUGUGACCAUCUAAUGCUCAGUUAAUUUCUAUUAUCUGACUUGUCCAGGUUACCAGCUUGAUCUGAUUUUUACAGUUUUAUUGCUCACAGCCUAUUAUAUCUUCACAGCACUUUUUUCUGUGACCAACAGCCUGGUUUUAGUAACUCUGGAUUUCCCAUGUCCAUUAUUUGAUUAUGUUAAUGCUUUCUAAAACACAAAUAAAUUGUUUUCUCAAUUC